AACCCGCUCGGAUCCCCUUUCAUACUGUGGAAGUUUUGUUCUUUCUCUGUUUGCAAUAAAUCUUCCUGCUGCUAACUCUUUGGGUCCACACUGCCUUUAUGAGCUGUAACACCGCGAAGGUCUGCAGCUUCACUCCUGAAGCCAGCAAGACCACGAGCCCACCAGGAGGAACGAACAACUCCAGACGCACUGCCUUAAGAGCUGUUAACACUCACGGCGAAAGUCUGCAGCUUCACUCCUGAGCCAGCGAGACCACAUAACCCACCAGAAGGAAGAAACCCCGAACAUAUCCGAACAUCAGAAGGAACAAACUCCAGGUGCGCCACCUUAAGAGCUAUAACACUCACCGCGAGGGUCCGCGGCUUCAUUCUUGAAGUCAAUGAGACCAAGAACCCACCAAUUCGAGACACAUCAUGAACCUUGGUUGGAGCAGCUCGGAGAGGCACAUGCUCAUCACAAAGCUGGCACAGAAUUGCUGUCUCAGUGACCUGCAUGUGCUGGUUGGUCCCCCCUCGGGCCUUUUACACAUGUCCACCCCUCCCACAGCUCCAUCCUCUGGUGUCACUGUCCGUGGAGCCACACAAACUUCUCAUGCUCUGCAGCCAAUGGUGAUUAACGGAACUGGGAUGCCCCAUACUCUGCAAGGAACUCCCUGGAGGGAGAAAUCUUCUGGAGUAUGAGCCAGCAAUUAGCUGCCCUGUUCAGGCUGUGUGCCCACCGCCUCAUCUCUUCUCGGUGGGACUCCAGGCCCUCCAAGCGUCCUGACAGCAGGCCUCAGCCAUGAGGGUCCAGGUACUUAGCUGGAGAUCCCCGUGCACAAUUACCUGCGUCACUUUCAGUUUACCUUCCUCUUGUCUGGAAGAACAGAGAAUUCUUGCAAUAGAAGCUUUGUGAUAUCACAAAGCUGGGGACUUACUGGAAAAAUGUGAGACUCACACACCUGGCCAGGAGGAAAAAACUCAGGACUGCAGUGGACAUUUGUCCAAUUGGUGGCCAACAAUGAGCUUUGAGUAAAUUUUCUAUAUUGAAGGAGCUUCUCAUCUUAUGCAUGCCAUCUCUGCAAAUUAGAAGCUGGGACUCAAUUUUCCAGUCUCUCUUGCAACUAGGAUAUAGACAUGUGACCUGUGCUCUGGCCAUUAGUUGCAGCCUUUUGAGAUUUUCAUUCACAACAUAAAAUGCGAAAAAGCAGGCACUGACUGAAUCCAUUCCUGGAGUACUUUGUGAAGAAAUAUGGGAACCUUUUUAGCUUGGAGCUUGGUGACAUAUCUGCAGUUCUUAUUACUGGCUUGCCCUUAAUCAAAGAAGCCCUUAUCCACAUGGACCAAAACUUUGGGAACCGCCCCGUGACCCCUAUGCGAGAACAUAUCUUUAAGAAAAAUGGAUUGAUUAUGUCAAGUGGCCAGGCAUGGAAGGAGCAAAGAAGGUUCACUCUGACAGCACUAAGGAACUUUGGUUUAGGAAAGAAGAGCUUAGAGGAACGCAUUCAGGAGGAGGCCCAACACCUCACUGAAGCAAUAAAAGAGGAGAACGGACAGCCUUUUGACCCUCAUUUCAAGAUCAACAAUGCAGUUUCCAAUAUCAUUUGCUCCAUCACCUUCGGAGAACGCUUUGAGUACCAGGAUAGUUGGUUUCAGCAGCUGCUGAAGUUACUAGAUGAAGUCACAUACUUGGAGGCUUCAAAGACAUGCCAGCUCUACAAUGUCUUUCCAUGGAUAAUGAAAUUCCUGCCUGGACCCCACCAAACUCUCUUCAGCAACUGGAAAAAACUGAAAUUGUUUGUUUCUCAUAUGAUUGACAAACACAGAAAGGAUUGGAAUCCUGCAGAAACAAGAGACUUUAUUGAUGCUUACCUUAAAGAAAUGUCAAAGCACACAGGCAAUCCUACUUCAAGUUUCCAUGAAGAAAACCUCAUCUGCAGCACCCUGGACCUCUUCUUUGCCGGAACCGAGACAACUUCCACAACUCUGCGAUGGGCUCUGCUUUAUAUGGCCCUCUACCCAGAAAUCCAAGAAAAAGUACAAGCUGAGAUUGACAGAGUGAUUGGCCAGGGGCAGCAGCCGAGCACAGCCGCCCGGGAGUCCAUGCCCUACACCAAUGCUGUCAUCCAUGAGGUGCAGAGAAUGGGCAACAUCAUCCCCCUGAACGUUCCCAGGGAAGUGACAGUUGAUACCACUUUGGCUGGGUACCACCUGCCCAAGGGUACCAUGAUCCUGACCAAUUUGACGGCGCUGCACAGGGACCCCACAGAGUGGGCCACCCCUGACACAUUCAAUCCGGACCAUUUUCUGGAGAAUGGACAGUUUAAGAAAAGGGAAGCCUUUAUGCCUUUCUCAAUAGGAAAGCGGGCAUGCCUCGGAGAACAGUUGGCCAGGACUGAGCUGUUUAUUUUCUUCACUUCCCUUAUGCAAAAAUUUACCUUCAGGCCCCCAAACAAUGAGAAGCUGAGCCUGAAGUUUAGAAUGGGUAUCACCAUUUCCCCAGUCAGUCACCGCCUCUGCGCUGUUCCUCAGGUGUAAUAUUGUUAAGAAAGAAAGGGGCAAGGAAAGUAAGAAGACAUGGCACGUGUUCUGAAACCACUGGUGUCUGCUCAGAUGUGUUGGGACAAAAUGAAAGUGACUUUCAAGAAAGAUCAGAGGAAUUUGACUCAGAGAAAACUAGAUCCAAAUCCCAGCUCUACUGUCUCGUCCGAAUUAGCCUUGGGAAAAUCAUUUAUAUGCUAAAUAAUUUACCUUUUUAUCUAGGAGAUGAAAAGAGGAUAAUGUUUCCUUCCAUAAAGAAAGUUCUUGUAAGAAUCAAAAGAAAUGGUGAGCUUUAAGUGGUUUGUAAACCAUAAAACACAUCAUAAAAGUUCUAUCUAUA